AGUGCGCCGGAGGAACUGUGCUCUUUGAGGCCGACGCUAGGGGCCCGGAAGGGAAACUGCGAGGCGAAGGUGACCGGGGACCGAGCAUUUCAGAUCUGCUCGGUAGACCUGGUGCACCACCACCAUGUUGGCUGCAAGGCUGGUGUGUCUCCGGACACUACCUUCUAGGGUUUUCCACCCAGCUUUCACCAAGGCCUCCCCUGUUGUGAAGAAUUCCAUCACGAAGAAUCAAUGGCUGUUAACACCUAGCAGGGAAUAUGCCACCAAAACAAGAAUUGGGAUCCGGCGUGGGAGAACUGGCCAAGAACUCAAAGAGGCAGCAUUGGAACCAUCGAUGGAAAAAAUAUUUAAAAUUGAUCAGAUGGGAAGAUGGUUUGUUGCUGGAGGGGCUGCUGUUGGUCUUGGAGCAUUGUGCUACUAUGGCUUGGGACUGUCUAAUGAGAUUGGAGCUAUUGAAAAGGCUGUAAUUUGGCCUCAGUAUGUCAAGGAUAGAAUUCAUUCCACCUAUAUGUACUUAGCAGGGAGUAUUGGUUUAACAGCUUUGUCUGCCAUAGCAAUCAGCAGAACGCCUGUUCUCAUGAACUUCAUGAUGAGAGGCUCUUGGGUGACAAUUGGUGUGACCUUUGCAGCCAUGGUUGGAGCUGGAAUGCUGGUACGAUCAAUACCAUAUGACCAGAGCCCAGGCCCAAAGCAUCUUGCUUGGUUGCUACAUUCUGGUGUGAUGGGUGCAGUGGUGGCUCCUCUGACAAUAUUAGGGGGUCCUCUUCUCAUCAGAGCUGCAUGGUACACAGCUGGCAUUGUGGGAGGCCUCUCCACUGUGGCCAUGUGUGCGCCCAGUGAAAAGUUUCUGAACAUGGGUGCACCCCUGGGAGUGGGCCUGGGUCUCGUCUUUGUGUCCUCAUUGGGAUCUAUGUUUCUUCCACCUACCACCGUGGCUGGUGCCACUCUUUACUCAGUGGCAAUGUACGGUGGAUUAGUUCUUUUCAGCAUGUUCCUUCUGUAUGAUACCCAGAAAGUAAUCAAGCGUGCAGAAGUAUCACCAAUGUAUGGAGUUCAAAAAUAUGAUCCCAUUAACUCGAUGCUGAGUAUCUACAUGGAUACAUUAAAUAUAUUUAUGCGAGUUGCAACUAUGCUGGCAACUGGAGGCAACAGAAAGAAAUGAAGUGACUCAGCUUCUGGCUUCUCUGCUACAUCAAAUAUCUUGUUUAAUGGGGCAGAUAUGCAUUAAAUAGUUUGUACAAGCAGCUUUCGUUGAAGUUUAGAAGAUAAGAAACAUGUCAUCAUAUUUAAAUGUUCCGGUAAUGUGAUGCCUCAGGUCUGCCUUUUUUUCUGGAGAAUAAAUGCAGUAAUCCUCUCCCAAAUAAGCACACACAUUUUCAAUUCUCAUGUUUGAGUGAUUUUAAAAUGUUUUGGUGAAUGUGAAAACUAAAGUUUGUGUCAUGAGAAUGUAAGUCUUUUUUCUACUUUAAAAUUUAGUAGGUUCACUGAGUAACUAAAAUUUAGCAAACCUGUGUUUGCAUAUUUUUUUGGAGUGCAGAAUAUUGUAAUUAAUGUCAUAAGUGAUUUGGAGCUUUGGUAAAGGGACCAGAGAGAAGGAGUCACCUGCAGUCUUUUGUUUUUUUAAAUACUUAGAACUUAGCACUUGUGUUAUUGAUUAGUGAGGAGCCAGUAAGAAACAUCUGGGUAUUUGGAAACAAGUGGUCAUUGUUACAUUCAUCUGCUGAACUUAACAAAACUGUUCAUCCUGAAACAGGCACAGGUGAUGCAUUCUCCUGCUGUUGCUUCUCAGUGCUCUCUUUCCAAUAUAGAUGUGGUCAUGUUUGACUUGUACAGAAUGUUAAUCAUACAGAGAAUCCUUGAUGGAAUUAUAUAUGUGUGUUUUACUUUUGAAUGUUACAAAAGGAAAUAACUUUAAAACUAUUCUCAAGAGAAAAUAUUCAAAGCAUGAAAUAUGUUGCUUUUUCCAGAAUACAAACAGUAUACUCAUGAUUGCUAAGUGUUUUUUUAUUUUUGCAUAUUUAUUGAACUGUCUAAUUGAAUACAGCUUGCUCUUGUCACCUCUUCAAGCUUUCAAGCCUUUAUAGAAAAGCUUCUUUGUGGCUUACACUGGAAAUUAUGAAAGCAGUUUUUCUCCUAAGACUUUUGGUUUCUCGCAUUGCCUCUCAGACUAAGCACUAAAAAGCAAAGCAAAACAGAACUAGUUCUGUCUUAAUGAAAUAUAUCAACCCAAAAGUGUAAUGAGGAAAAUGCUUCAUUAGUUUCCCCUAGCAGACUUUUACUUCUCUUACACUGCUACACCAUUACUUUCUUGAGACAUUUGUAAGUUCUUUGAUACAGAAGAGUUAUAUUUAGAAGUCUUUAAUGAAGGGAAAGAAGUCUGUA